UAGAGCAUCAGAUACUGGAGUUUGCCAGGGGUAGAAUGGUUGGAUUCAGGAAUGUUUAGCUGACUCAUAGCAGGAAGUUAUCCUGUAAAAAAAUGAAGCAAGGCAGGGAAGACAGAUUUAAGUACCAUGCAGCUCAAAACGACAAUUACAUUGUCAUUUUCGUUGUGAAUACUUCUAGGUUCUAUAUUGGCUGUGAUCUUUGUACUAACUGCUAUUAUGGAGAAUGUGUUGGCAUCGCAGAAAAGGAGGCUAAGAAAAUGGAUGUGUACAUCUGUAAUGAUUGUAAAUGGGCACAAGAGGGCAGCAGUGAGGAAUUGUACUGUAUCUGCAGAACACCUUUCGGAUCUUGCAGAUUUUUUAUUGGCCAUGAUCGGUGUCAGAAUUGGUACCAUGGGUGCUGCAUUGGCAUCUUGCAGAGUGAGGCAGAGCUCAUUGAUGAGUAUGUCUGUCCACAGUGCCAGUCAACAGAGGAUGUCAUGACAGUGCUCACACCACUAACAGAGAAGGAUGAUGAGGAGUUGAAGAGGGUGCUCCGUUCCUUACAGAUGAGAGCCCAUAAGAUGGCCCAGCCUUUCCUUGAACCAGUAGACCCUAAUGAUGCACCAGAUUAUUAUGGUGUUAUUAAGGAACCUGUGGGUACACAUGAGUUGAAUUUGAAGUUUUUUCAGAAGUCUCAGUGUAUAUUUUAUUAACCAUAAAAUUAAUAUCUUAGAAUACUUUUAGCAAGGCUGGUGGGGGUAUAAAUUGGUAUGGUCACUUUGGAGGGUAAAUUGAUAGUAUCUAUUACAGUUGAAUUGUGCAUACUCGGUUAUUUUAUUUUAUUUUUUUGAGAUGGAGUCUCACCCUGUUGCCAGGCUGGAGUGCAGUGGUGU